GAUGGCGCGCGACUGUUUCCCAUCUACUCAGAGGCUGAGGCGGGAGAAUCGCUUGAACCCGGAAGGCGGAGGUUGCAGUGAGCUGAAAUCACGCCAUUGCGCUCCAGCCUGGGUGACAGAGCAAGACUCCGUCACAAAAAAAAAAAGAAAAAAGAAACACCAGUUUUCUGAUUUCACCGAAGACCUACUGCCUCAGAAACUAUGAGGGCAGAACCCAGCAAUCUGUGCUUUCUUUCACAAGCCCUCCAGGAGUUGCUGAAAUUUAGGAAUCAUUGCCCCAAAAAGUGGCCCUCAUAAUGAUGCCAGAUGGGAUCUUACUCUGUUGCCCAGGCUGGAGUGCAGUGGUGCGAUCUCGGCUCUCUGCAACCUCCGCCUCCCAGGUUCAAGUGAUUCUCCUGCCUCGGCCUCCUGAGUAGCUGGGAUUUCAGGCCAUGAAAGAUCACUGUUUUAGUCUGCGUGGUGCAGUGGAACAGAUAGACCUCGGUUUGAAUCUCAGCUCUACUGUUUACUAGACAUGAAAUGGGGAAAUCUAAAAUGAGAUGCCAGAAGCCUCAAAAAUGGAAAACCCCCUGUGCUUCACAUCUGAAAAUCUCUGCUGGGGGCAGCAACUUUGAGCCUGUGGGGAAGGAACUGUCCACGUGGAGUGGUCUGGUGAAUGCUUAAGGAGCUGCAGAAGGGAAGUCCCUCUCCAAACUAGCCAGCCACUGAGACCUUCUGACAGGACACCCCCAGGAUGUCACCCAAAAAAGUACAAAUCAAAGUGGAGGAAAAAGAAGACGAGACUGAGGAAAGCUCAAGUGAAGAGGAAGAGGAGGUGGAAGAUAAGCUACCUCGAAGAGAGAGCUUGAGACCAAAGAGGAAACGGACCAGAGAUGUUAUCAAUGAGGAUGACCCAGAACCUGAACCAGAGGAUGAAGAAACAAGGAAGGCAAGAGAAAAAGAGAGGAGGAGGAGGCUAAAGAGAGGAGCAGAAGAAGAAGAAAUUGAUGAAGAGGAAUUGGAAAGAUUGAAGGCAGAGUUAGAUGAGAAAAGACAAAUAAUUGCUACUGUCAAAUGCAAACCAUGGAAGAUGGAGAAGAAAAUUGAAGUUCUCAAGGAGGCAAAAAAAUUUGUGAGUGAAAAUGAAGGGGCUCUUGGGAAAGGAAAAGGAAAACGGUGGUUUGCAUUUAAGAUGAUGAUGGCCAAGAAAUGGGCAAAAUUCCUCCGUGAUUUUGAGAACUUCAAAGCUGCGUGUGUCCCAUGGGAAAAUAAAAUCAAGGCUAUUGAAAGUCAGUUUGGCUCCUCAGUGGCCUCAUACUUCCUCUUCUUGAGAUGGAUGUAUGGAGUCAAUAUGGUUCUCUUUAUCCUGACAUUUAGCCUCAUCAUGUUGCCAGAGUACCUCUGGGGUUUGCCAUAUGGCAGUUUACCUAGGAAAACCGUUCCCAGAGCCGAAGAGGCAUCGGCAGCAAACUUUGGUGUGUUGUACGACUUCAAUGGUUUGGCACAAUAUUCCGUUCUCUUUUAUGGCUAUUAUGACAAUAAACGAACAAUUGGAUGGAUGAAUUUCAGGUUGCCGCUCUCCUAUUUUCUAGUGGGGAUUAUGUGCAUUGGAUACAGCUUUCUGGUUGUCCUCAAAGCAAUGACCAAAAACAUUGGUGAUGAUGGAGGUGGAGAUGACAACACUUUCAAUUUCAGCUGGAAGGUCUUUACCAGCUGGGACUACCUGAUCGGCAAUCCUGAAACAGCAGACAACAAAUUUAAUUCUAUCACAAUGAACUUUAAGGAAGCUAUCACAGAAGAAAAAGCAGCCCAAGUAGAAGAAAACGUCCACUUGAUCAGAUUCCUGAGGUUUCUGGCUAACUUCUUCGUGUUUCUAACACUUGGAGGGAGUGGAUACCUCAUCUUUUGGGCUGUGAAGCGAUCCCAGGAAUUUGCACAGCAAGAUCCUGACACCCUUGGGUGGUGGGAAAAAAAUGAAAUGAACAUGGUUAUGUCCCUCCUAGGGAUGUUCUGUCCAACAUUGUUUGACUUAUUUGCUGAAUUAGAAGACUACCAUCCUCUCAUCGCUUUGAAAUGGCUACUGGGACGCAUUUUUGCUCUUCUUUUAGGCAAUUUAUACGUAUUUAUUCUUGCAUUAAUGGAUGAGAUUAACAACAAGAUUGAAGAGGAGAAGCUAGUAAAGGCCAAUAUUACCCUUUGGGAAGCCAAUAUGAUCAAGGCCUACAAUGCAUCAUUCUCUGAAAAUAGCACUGGACCACCCUUUUUUGUUCACCCUGCAGAUGUACCUCGAGGACCUUGCUGGGAAACAAUGGUGGGACAGGAGUUUGUGAGGCUGACAGUCUCUGAUGUUCUGACCACCUACGUCACAAUCCUCAUUGGGGACUUUCUAAGGGCAUGUUUUGUGAGGUUUUGCAAUUAUUGCUGGUGCUGGGACUUGGAGUAUGGAUAUCCUUCAUACACCGAAUUCGACAUCAGUGGCAACGUCCUCGCUCUGAUCUUCAACCAAGGCAUGAUCUGGAUGGGCUCCUUCUUUGCUCCCAGCCUCCCAGGCAUCAAUAUCCUUCGACUCCAUACAUCCAUGUACUUCCAGUGCUGGGCCGUUAUGUGCUGCAAUGUUCCUGAGGCCAGGGUCUUCAAAGCUUCCAGAUCAAAUAACUUCUACCUGGGCAUGCUACUGCUCAUCCUCUUCCUGUCCACAAUGCCUGUCUUGUACAUGAUCGUGUCCCUCCCACCAUCUUUUGAUUGUGGUCCAUUCAGUGGCAAAAAUAGAAUGUUUGAAGUCAUUGGAGAGACCCUGGAGCACGAUUUCCCAAGCUGGAUGGCGAAGAUCUUGAGACAGCUUUCAAACCCUGGGCUGGUCAUUGCUGUCAUUUUGGUGAUGGUUUUGGCCAUCUAUUAUCUCAAUGCUACUGCCAAGGGCCAGAAGGCAGCGAAUCUGGAUCUCAAAAAGAAGAUGAAAAUGCAAGCUUUGGAGAACAAAAUGCGAAACAAGAAAAUGGCAGCUGCACGAGCAGCUGCAGCUGCUGGUCGCCAGUAAUAAGUAUCCUGAGAGCCCAGAAAAGGUACACUUUGCCUUGCUGUUUAAAAGUAAUGCAAUAUGUGAACGCCCAGAGAACAAGCACUGUGGAACUGCUAUUUUCCUGUUCUACCCUUGAUGGAUUUUCAAGGUCAUGCUGGCCAAUUAAGGCAUCAUCAGUCCUACCUGAGCAACAAGAAUCUAAACUUUAUUCCAAGUCAGAAACUGUUUCUGCAGAGCCACUCUCUCCCCUGCUCCAUUUCGUGACUUUUUUUUUUUUUUUAACAAAUUGAGUUUAGAAGUGAGUGUAAUCCAGCAAUACAGUUUACUGGUUUAGUUGGUGGGUUAAUUAAAAAAAAUUUGCUCAUAUGAACUUUCAUUUUAUAUGUUUCUUUUGCCUGAGUUUCCUUAAACUGAGAGCAGAAAUAUUUCACCCUUUUUCCUCUAAGUUCAGAAAUAUUUGCAAAAAGUACUCAUUGUAAUCAUUCAUUAACUCACUUUUUGAAACCAAUACCUUAUUUUCUCUUUUUUUCUACCUGUCUCCCCAACCACGCGCCCCACAAAUAUAUUCCUAAAACCUUUGUAUUUGGUGCUGGAUUCAGUAUGAAAAGAAAUAGGGUUUUUAGAAGAAAAAAAAAUCCUAUAUGAAUUGGGGCCUGGAUAGCACUGAGUUGAAGAUCUUGAAGAUCUCUUACUUUGAGAAGGUACAUGAGUCUUACACAACCUAGCUUUUUAUGAGAUAAAAUUAAAAAAAAAAGGAAAGACAUCAUAAAUGACUGUUGUUCUCUCACAGUCUGCUCAUUUGUCUUCCAAUGAUCAUGUUAUCAGUGGUGAAUCCAUACAGGUCUGCAUCAAACUCGAUACAAUUCUUGCCUCCUUGGAGGGAAGAAUUCAGCUGAGGGGCAGAAGUAGGUUUAUGGCAGAGGGAGAGAAUGAGGCAAGUUUUAGAGCAGGAGUGUAGGUUUAUUAAAAAGUUUUACAGCAGGAACAAAAGGAAAUAAAAUAUACUUGGAAGAGAGCCAAGUGGGCAAAUUGAGAGUUCCAAGUGCCCUGUUCAGCUUUGACCUGGGUUUCUAUACACUGGCAUGGUUCUGGAGUUUGCAUCUCUCCCCGCUUGAUUUUUUUGGCGGAUGGGCUGUCCGUGUGGAUGGUGGCCUGCCGGCAGUUGGAAGGAGCUAUGUGUACAAUGUGUUACUGAAGUUGUGUGCCUGCUCACUUGUGACGUUUUCCCUUACCAUCCAGCGUUCCUGGAGGAAGGUCAUAUACUAGUUAAACUCUGCCAUUUUGCUUAGUGGGCAUGCUUGAGCCCACUUGCCCAACUCCUAAGAUCUCCGGCUCAGGUGUUUUCUAUCUAUUGGGAGACUGUCUUUCCCUAGCACUGGUUGCCACUAAUUAUUAUUUUAGAGAGAUAGUUUAACCACCACCUGACCAUCACCAAAUGGUCACCUGACAUUCCUGUGGGAUGGGUGGUGGGGGGCCUCUCUUGCCCUGCUUAUGUUUUUAUGUUUGCCUAACUACCUACUCUAACAAUCAUAUCCUGUAAGCUUGGAUUCUAAUGUUCUAUAAUUUUUUUCUUUGCUUUUUUUGUUAAGGUCAGGAAAACACACUUCUGUUGGGGGCCUUAAUUUAUAGAUAUGUUUAAGCAUUAUUAUGGAUUUACAGUUUGAAUUGACUUUAAGUAGUAACACUCAGUGCCCUCACUAGCCUUGUUGUGCGACUUUAAUUGCAUAGCUUAACUCAGUGUGCCUUUCCAAAACUAAGCCAAUUUGCUUGCCAUUCCCUGCAGUUGACUUACUGAUUUCUAUUAUCCUGUCUCUGAGUUUCUCAUUCUUUUUGAUCACCAAAAGGCAGCCAUAGAAUAAUCGCACUGUUUCCCUGCCAGUUCUAAACUUUAUUCCUCUGGUUGUCUUUUUCAGAUUGACUUCCAUUCUCAAUCUUAUCACUCCCUUUUUAGGAUUCCUUGGGCUCUUAUGUCUGUAAUUCAGAGUCUAUUAUUUAUAUUGAUUUUCAUGUGACUUGUAAUGGUUCCUUAUUAUUUUUUGAUGCAUGGAUUAUCUUUCUUGUCCUUAUUGUAAAUUCUCUGUGAGCAGGGGUUGUAUCUUCUAACUCUUUUGUAUGCCUAGUAUAGUGCUGUGCACAAGUAGGCGCUGAAUAAAUGCUUGCUAAUUAAAUUGAAUCAAUUUAACUUACAGCAAUUGUGUUAUGAGACAAAAACUUCUGUUACCUGCAUGAAAACAUUUUACUAUGAUGUAAGAAAUGGAUUAUCUGUUGAUAGGCUGAGUUUAUUGUUUAAUUAGAUUAUAAUGCAGAUGAGUAAAUAAAGCUAGUGUUUAUUUCUACUUGGA